GAAUUCCAUGGCGGCGCGGCGGCGACGGAGCACCGGCGGCGGCAGGGCGAGAGCAUUAAAUGAAAGCAAAAGAGUUAAUAAUGGCAACACGGCUCCAGAAGACUCUUCCCCUGCCAAGAAAACUCGUAGAUGCCAGAGACAGGAGUCGAAAAAGAUGCCUGUGGCUGGAGGAAAAGCUAAUAAGGACAGGACAGAAGACAAGCAAGAUGGUAUGCCAGGAAGGUCAUGGGCCAGCAAAAGGGUCUCUGAAUCUGUGAAGGCCUUGCUGUUAAAGGGCAAAGCUCCUGUGGACCCAGAGUGUACAGCCAAGGUGGGGAAGGCUCAUGUGUAUUGUGAAGGAAAUGAUGUCUAUGAUGUCAUGCUAAAUCAGACCAAUCUCCAGUUCAACAACAACAAGUACUAUCUGAUUCAGCUAUUAGAAGAUGAUGCCCAGAGGAACUUCAGUGUUUGGAUGAGAUGGGGCCGAGUUGGGAAAAUGGGACAGCACAGCCUGGUGGCUUGUUCAGGCAAUCUCAACAAGGCCAAGGAAAUCUUUCAGAAGAAAUUCCUUGACAAAACGAAAAACAAUUGGGAAGAUCGAGAAAAGUUUGAGAAGGUGCCUGGAAAAUAUGAUAUGCUACAGAUGGACUAUGCCACCAAUACUCAGGAUGAAGAGGAAACAAAGAAAGAGGAAUCUCUUAAAUCUCCCUUGAAGCCAGAGUCACAGCUAGAUCUUCGGGUACAGGAGUUAAUAAAGUUGAUCUGUAAUGUUCAGGCCAUGGAAGAAAUGAUGAUGGAAAUGAAGUAUAAUACCAAGAAAGCCCCACUUGGGAAGCUGACAGUGGCACAAAUCAAGGCAGGUUACCAGUCUCUUAAGAAGAUUGAGGAUUGUAUUCGGGCUGGCCAGCAUGGACGAGCUCUCAUGGAAGCAUGCAAUGAAUUCUACACCAGGAUUCCGCAUGACUUUGGACUCCGUACUCCUCCACUAAUCCGGACACAGAAGGAACUGUCAGAAAAAAUACAAUUACUAGAGGCUUUGGGAGACAUUGAAAUUGCUAUUAAGCUGGUGAAAACAGAGCUACAAAGCCCAGAACACCCAUUGGACCAACACUAUAGAAACCUACAUUGUGCCUUGCGCCCCCUUGACCAUGAAAGUUAUGAGUUCAAAGUGAUUUCCCAGUACCUACAAUCUACCCAUGCUCCCACACACAGCGACUAUACCAUGACCUUGCUGGAUUUGUUUGAAGUGGAGAAGGAUGGUGAGAAAGAAGCCUUCAGAGAGGACCUUCAUAACAGGAUGCUUCUAUGGCAUGGUUCCAGGAUGAGUAACUGGGUGGGAAUCUUGAGCCAUGGGCUUCGAAUUGCCCCACCUGAAGCUCCCAUCACAGGUUACAUGUUUGGGAAAGGAAUCUACUUUGCUGACAUGUCUUCCAAGAGUGCCAAUUACUGCUUUGCCUCUCGCCUAAAGAAUACAGGACUGCUGCUCUUAUCAGAGGUAGCUCUAGGUCAGUGUAAUGAACUACUAGAGGCCAAUCCUAAGGCCGAAGGAUUGCUUCAAGGUAAACAUAGCACCAAGGGGCUGGGCAAGAUGGCUCCCAGUUCUGCCCACUUCGUCACCCUGAAUGGGAGUACAGUGCCAUUAGGACCAGCAAGUGACACAGGAAUUCUGAAUCCAGAUGGUUAUACCCUCAACUACAAUGAAUAUAUUGUAUAUAACCCCAACCAGGUCCGUAUGCGGUACCUUUUAAAGGUUCAGUUUAAUUUCCUUCAGCUGUGGUGAAUGUUGAUAUUAAAUAAACCAGAGAUCUGAUCUUCAAGCAAGAAAAUAAGCAGUGUUGUACUUGUGAAUUUUGUGAUAUUUUAUGUAAUAAAAACUGUACAGGUCUA